GUAUUUUUCCUAUGCCCGGUCCGUGCAUUCUGGUUGUGAAGGCUGAGUUCUAGAGAUCGGGUCGGCUUUCUACGCGGCUCUCGUGGAACCUAGCAAAGAAAGACAGUGAAGACUGCAGGACCUUCCUUCGCGCUUUUGUUACAAUCCAUGACCCCUGUCGUGGGACGGGCGGCCUCUCGCGGAGGUGUCUGCCGGGGCUGGGCUCUUACCGAGGCCUCCACACACGUCCUCUUGUCCUUGUCUCCCCCAGAAGCAGCCGCCUUAGUCUUGUGAGCGUUUUUACACCGGGUAGAUUGAGACUUGGAGUGCUACACUCAGCCCGAGGGCGUCCAGCGCGGUGGAGGCGUGGGGUUUCGGCUGAGCCCACAGGGCACAGACUGUUCAUCCGCUUCUCAUGGCAGCGGCGGUGCUGAUGGACCGGGUUCAGAGUUGUGUGACCUUCGAGGAUGUGUUCGUGUACUUCUCUCGGGAGGAGUGGGAACUCCUUGAGGAGGCACAGAGAUUCCUGUACCGUGAUGUGAUGCUGGAGAACUUUGCACUUGUGGCUACACUAGCUUUCAUUUUCCCAGUCCCAUGCAGUUGCGCAGUUGGAGGGGGCAGAAAACCUUGGGUGCCUGACAGGGCAGACAUCACUGCAGCCACAGUAAAGGAGACCUACAGAGGGCAUGGCCCUGCUGAAUGGGAGCUGGAAGAGGGUAUCUGUUAUGGUUGGGUUCAAAUCGAACCUUCAACUUGUUUUGUGUUUGUCAGUGUUUUGUUGCCAAGGCCCAUAGUGAUUCUUCACAUCUACUUUACUUUCCUCAUUCUUGGCACUUUUUCCAUUUGUCAUUUCUCACGUGUCUUCCAUCCUUUGGGUGUUUUCCCACUUUUCUGGCCUCCGUGUUUCAAUUGCUCUCUUCAACACUAGCUUACUUUAAUGUGUCAUGAGUUCUGCACAUUAAAUAGUCCGUGAGAAUGAGCUACUUAUUUGGAGUCAGAUUUUCGUGGGCAUGGACAUACCCAUCUGCACAGAGCUCACCUGACACCAGCGGCCAAGGCCCUGCUGAAACUCUCUUGCAGAGGAAUCAGGUUUUUGGUGUGAAGCAGAACAUGAGGCACCUUCUGAGCAGAGCGUUUCUGUAGAAGGAGUGUCACAGGUCAGGACUGCUGAGUCAGGUCUUUUCCAGAAAGCACACCCAUGUGAGAUGUGUGACCCACUCUUGAAAGACAUUUUGCACCUGGCUGAACACCAGGGAUCACACCUUACACAGAAACUGUGCACACGUGGGCUGUGUAGGAGAAGAUUCUCGUUCAGUGCAAACUUUUACCAGCACCAGAAGCAACAUAAUGGAGAGAAUUGCUUCAGAGGGGAUGAUGGAGGGGCCUCAUUUGUGAAGAGCUGUACAGUCCACAUGUUAGGGAGAUCCUUUACGUGCAGGGAGGAAGGGAUGGACUUACCAGAUAGCUCUGGCCUUUUCCAGCACCAGACCACUUACAAUAGGGUGAGUCCAUGCAGAAGGACUGAAUGCAUGGAGUCUUUCCCACACAGCUCCAGUCUCAGGCAACACCAAGGAGACUAUGAUGGACAGAUGCUUUUCAGUUGCGGUGAUGAAGGGAAAGCCUUCCUGGACACCUUUACUCUUCUUGACAGCCAGAUGACUCAUGCUGAGGUGAGACCCUUCAGAUGCCUACCAUGUGGAAAUGUGUUCAAGGAGAAAUCAGCUCUUAUUAAUCACAGAAAAAUCCACAGUGGAGAAAUAUCUCAUGUGUGUAAGGAGUGUGGAAAAGCCUUCAUUCACUUGCACCACCUAAAAAUGCACCAGAAAUUUCACACUGGAAAAAGACACUAUACAUGCAGUGAAUGUGGGAAGGCCUUCAGCCGCAAGGACACACUUGUUCAGCAUCAGAGAGUUCACACUGGAGAAAGAUCUUAUGACUGCAGUGAAUGUGGAAAAGCCUACAGCAGAAGCUCCCACCUUGUUCAGCACCAGAGAAUUCACACAGGAGAAAGGCCUUAUAAGUGCAACAAAUGUGGGAAAGCCUUUAGCCGUAAAGACACACUUGUUCAGCACCAGAGAUUUCAUACUGGAGAAAGGCCUUAUGAGUGCAGUGAAUGUGGAAAAUUCUUUAGCCAAAGCUCCCACCUUAUUGAGCACUGGAGAAUUCAUACCGGGGCAAGGCCCUAUGAAUGCAUAGAAUGUGGAAAAUUCUUUAGCCAUAACUCUAGCCUCAUUAAACAUCGGAGAGUCCACACAGGAGCAAGAUCCUACGUGUGCAGCAAAUGUGGGAAGGCCUUUGGCUGCAAAGACACACUUGUUCAGCACCAGAUAAUUCACACUGGAGCAAGGCCUUAUGAGUGCAGUGAAUGUGGGAAGGCCUUCAGCCGUAAAGACACACUUGUGCAACACCAAAAAAUCCACACUGGAGAAAGGCCUUAUGAGUGUGGUGAAUGUGGUAAAUUCUUCAGCCAUAGCUCCAACCUUAUUGUACACCAGAGAAUUCACACUGGAGCAAAGCCUUAUGAGUGCAAUGAAUGUGGGAAAUGCUUUAGCCACAACUCCAGCCUCAUUUUGCACCAGAGAGUUCACACAGGAGCAAGGCCUUAUGUGUGCAGUGAAUGUGGGAAGGCUUACAUUAGUAGCUCCCACCUUGUUCAACACAAGAAAGUUCACACUGGAGCAAGACCUUAUGAGUGCAGUGAAUGUGGGAAAUUCUUUAGCCGCAACUCUGGCCUCAUUCUGCACCAGAGGGUUCACACUGGAGAAAAGCCUUACGUAUGCAGCGAAUGUGGGAAAGCCUAUAGCAGAAGCUCCCAUCUUGUUCGUCACCAGAAAGCUCACACUGGAGAAAGAGCUCACGAGUGCAACAGUUUUGGUGGCCCUUUAGCUGCAUCUCUUAAACUUGUUUAACACCAGAAAAUUCACACAAGAGAAAGGCCUUAUGAAUGCAGAAAAUAUGUCAUCUUGUUCAUCCUCAUAGGACUCACACCAGAGCAAUGCUCUGUGAGUACCCUUUGUGAGGGAACCAUCAGCUAGCAGAUGAGCACCGUAUAUUCAUUCCACCCUGGGGAGAUUCCUGAUAAGCACCACAUAUGUGGGAGGCUUUCAUGAGGUGUGUUGCACUUUGUAACUGUCUAGAGCUCUUGAUGGAAUUAUAUCACUGCCAGUGCCUGUGGCGGAAGCCAUCUUAUUGCUACCAGCUGUGUGUGUCAAUCACUCCAUUUUGCUCAGGGAAGGCAGACUUCUGUGCUUUCUUUCCUGUUCCCUACAGGUAAUCAUGAAUAUUUUCAAGGACUUCCCCCCCCCCCCACUUCACCCCCUACCAUUGAGGGUCCUCAUCUUUUCCCUCAUGAUUAGGUUCUGAGCAAACAUGAUCUAGCUCUCACCAAAAGGACCUGAGCUAGGGUCUGCUGGGAUUUCCUGACACGAUUUUCCAUCUUCAUGGACAAUGUUAACUGUAAACGUGAUAGCUGUGACUUACUUGUCUUACUGCCAAAUCGCCCAAAUUUGGAACUGCUUGUCCCAUGCUGCUCUGAUUUAUACAGUGAUAAGGGCCUAUUGUGGCAGUCUUUACUCUUGGGGAUUUUGUUACUGUGUAGAGUGGAUUGAGAAAAGAAUUGGGUUCUGUCAUGAAGGGAGUAGCACCUUUUGUGGGCACCACCUUUAUGUGCCUCAGAGGGGACCAAAGGAUGGCAGAAAACUGUUCUCAGUCUAGUUUGACCUAAUUUACACUAUUGCCCUAGGCUUGCUAGGAAAGACUGAAAAAAUUUUUGUGCCUAACUUUGUGGCCUGGCUGCCAGGAUUUCCUGUGAGCCCAGUGAGGAGGGCAUAGUUGGUGCGAAAAUCUCCUGUGCUUGUGGAAGCAACAUAAGUUGGGUCCCUUAACUGUCACGUACUCCCCAGCACUGUUGAGGGAUUGCUGUCUUCUGUACCUGUACAGGAUCAAGUCCCUGAUAUCCAGAACCCCAUAGGCAAGUAACAUUGACUGUAAGACCUCUGUAGGGCAAUGUGAAAAUCAUGAUUGCUACAGAAGCACUGAGAUAAUGGAGUGGGGAUGACUGUGGCAAACAAAAGGAGAUUCGAACAUUCUAGAGGGGCAUCCACAAGUCUCGGUGCAGUUAUGAUGGUGUGGGAUGGGAGUGCAUAGAAAUUCUCAGGACCUUCAGACAUCUGUAUCUCCUGUGGCCAAGGCCACUGUCAGAGGAAAUAAUCUAAAUGUUUGUGGAUUCCUGUGUCUCCCUGGGCAGUUGACCUGCACAGACAGGAACCUCAGCAGUGACAGAAGAGAGAUCCAGGGAUGGGUCUUCUCUGACCCAGCCAGCAUUCCGAGUGACUGAGGUGGAUGUGGACAUCAUUGCUUACCAAUUUUUACCAACAUUGAGGCAGGGCUCACUCUCCUAAAUUGUAGGGAGAGGAAUAUGGUAAAGCCAAAAUAGUUGACAGAUCUAACUUUCCUAGUGGAACAGUAUAUAUAGAUUUUAAUGAGGAACAUUUAUUUAAUAGCUUUAUGGAGGUAUGAUUAACAUGCAAUAAACUGCAAAUAUGUAAAGUGUAAAAUGUGCUGUUUCAGCAUGUGUGUACACCUAUGAAACCACCACAGUCAAGAUAUCCAACACAACAAAAGAUUGUCCCUUUAUAAUCCUCAAUUUUUCCUUAUCUUGUUUUCCACAAUUCACAAGCAACAGCAAGCAUUUUCUAUAAUUUUAUAAAUGAAACCAUAUGGUGUGUACUUUUUAGGGGGUGGGGCUCUGGCUUUUUCAGUAAACAUAACUAUUUUAAGGUUAAUCCAUUAUCUUGUUGCAUGAAUCAAUUGUUUGCUCAUUUGUAUUGCUGCGUAGUAUUUCAGUAUUUCAUUGUAUACCACAAUUUUUCUUCUUUGUCAACUUAAUUGUUAUGGAUGUUUGGGUAACUUUCAGUUUUUGGCUAUUACAAAUAAACCUCUGAAGAUUUGUGUGCAAA